UUUUUUUUUUUUUUUUUUAAAGAGAUAGGGGUCUUGCUAUGUUGCUCAGUCUGGUCUUGAACUCCUGGCCUCAUGUGAUCCUCUCGCCCUGGCUUCUCAAGUAGCUGGGGUGACAAGCCUGUACCAUCACGCUACUCUUAACUGUGACUAUGCUUGAUUACUCUGUUUGGUCUUGGCAUAUCUGAAAAUAAGACCCAGAGAGGGAAAAUGCUUGGCAGACAUACCCCACAAGAAGAAUCACCUGAGUUAUAGUUCUGGAAGGGUCUUAUGUGUAAAAGACCUGCUGACAUAUGUAUACCUUGAGGUAGGGAUUCCCAAUCCCCAGGUGGUGGACCUGUACUAACCCAUGGACUGUUAGGAACUGGGCGGCAUAGCAGGAGGUGAGCGGUGAAUCAGCAGUACUGCCUGAGCUCCACCGCCUGUCAGAUCAGCAGCAUUAGAUUCUCAUAGGAGUUCAAACCCUAUUAUGAACUGCGCCUGGGAGGGAUCUAGGUUGCAUGCUCCUUAAUUGUCUUCCACAAAACUGGUCACUGGUGCCAAAAAGAUUGGGGAUUGCUGCUUUAGGGUGACAGUUUUCUGCAAUUCAGAUACAAGCUCUUUGUAUACAGGACUUGAAGAAGCCUGUUUUCCACCAUGAAAUAAAACAGGACCUAGGUGGGGUUUCUUUAACAGUUUACUUAGUUGGCACUAAGUAUGGCAUUAGGCAAAAGGCAGGGGAAGGUAGAUUAUGUUGGCAUGGUCCAACAGAAAUAUAAUGUAAGCCACAUAUGUAAUUAAAAAUUUCCUACUAGUCAUGUUAAAAGUAAGAAACAGGUAAAAUUAAUUUUAAUAAUAUAUUUUAUUUAACUCAUAUCCAAAAUAUUAUAGUUUCAUCAUAUGAUUAAUAUUAAAAAAAUGUAAUAUUUUAUGUAUUUUUUCAUAUUAAGUCUUUGAAACUCCACAUGCAUUUUGGUUUUCUUUUUUUUUUGAGAUGGAGUUUUGCUCUUGUCACCCAGGCUGAAGUGCAAUGGUGUGAUCUCGGCUCACUGCAACCUCUGCCUCCCAGGUUCAAAUGAUUCUCCUGCCUCGGCUUCCUGAGUAGCUGGGAUUACAGGCACCUGCCACCACGCCCAGCUAAUUUUUAUGUUUUUACUAGAGACGGGGUUUCAUCAUGUUGGCCAGCUGGUCUCAAACUCCUGACCUCAGGUGAUCCACCUGCCUCGGCCUCCCAAAGUGCUGGGAUUACAGGUGUGAGCCACUGCGCCUGGCCUCCAUGUGCAUUUGAUGCAUACUGCAUGCAUUUCCAGUGGGACUAGCUAUGUUAAAUGUGCCCAGUAGCUAUGUAUGGCUGGAGGCUAUCAUAUUGGAUAGUCUAUUAGUAGAAAAAUAUAUUAAGACAGCCUUGCAGAUAGCUCCUUAUGCCCGGACCCAGAGUUUGGAACGAUAUAUAUAAAAAUAAUUAUUAUUGUUUCAGUUAACAACAGGGACUGUAAAUGUAGUGGGUUCCAGGUUGAGAGUGCUAGAAAGAACCAUAGCUAUUUUAUCUAACAUUCACCCCCCCAUCCCCAUUUUUAUAGGUGAAGGCUUGUAUGCUCAACAACAUGUGUGAGGUCACACAGAGAGUCAUUGGCAUCGUCAAGACUCAAACCCAGUUGAUCUUUCUGAUGAUGAACCAGGUGGAAGGGCAGCAGAAGAACCUUGUGCACGCCAUUGAGUCCCUGCCAGGGUCCGGCCCCCUCACUGCCUUGGACCAGGACCUGCUGCUCCUGAAAGCUACCUCUGCUGCCACCCUCAGCUGCCUUGGGGAGUGCCUCAACUUGUUACAGCAGAGUGUGCACCAGGCGGGCCAGCCCAGCCAGAAGCCAGGAGCCUCGGAAAACAUCCUGGGAUGGCACGGGUCCAAGUCACAUUCCACAGAGCAGCUGAAAAAUGGGACACUUGGCUCUUUGCCAUCAGCCAGUGCCAACAUAACCUGGGCAAUUUUACCAAACUCUGCUGAAGACGAACAAACCUCACAGCCAGAGCCAGAGCCAAACUCAGGCUCUGAAUUGGUUUUGUCUGAAGAUGAAAAAAGUGACAAUGAAGAUAAGGAAGAGACGGAAUUGGGCGUCAUGGAGGAUCAGCGUAGUAUAAUUCUUCAUCUCAUUUCACAACUCAAACUUGGAAUGGAUUUGACCAAGGUGGUGCUUCCCACCUUUAUCCUGGAGAAGCGAUCUUUGCUGGAGAUGUAUGCAGAUUUCAUGGCGCACCCAGACCUACUGCUGGCCAUCACCGCUGGGGCCACACCAGAGGAGAGAGUCAUUUGCUUCGUUGAGUAUUAUCUCACAGCCUUUCACGAGGGCCGCAAGGGCGCUUUAGCCAAGAAGCCCUACAACCCCAUCAUAGGCGAGACAUUUCACUGCUCCUGGGAAGUUCCCAAGGACAGGGUCAAGCCUAAGAGGACUGCUUCCCGCUCUCCUGCCAGCUGUCACGAACACCCAAUGGCCGAUGACCCUUCCAAAAGCUACAAACUAAGGUUUGUGGCUGAGCAAGUGUCCCAUCACCCACCCAUCUCCUGCUUCUACUGUGAGUGCGAGGAGAAGAGACUGUGCGUCAACACUCAUGUAUGGACCAAAAGCAAGUUCAUGGGCAUGUCCGUGGGGGUCUCUAUGAUAGGGGAAGGUGUGUUGAGGCUCCUGGAACACGGGGAGGAGUACGUAUUCACCCUGCCUAGUGCCUACGCCCGGUCCAUUCUCACCAUCCCGUGGGUGGAGCUCGGAGGAAAAGUCAGCAUCAACUGUGCCAAGACUGGGUACUCAGCGACAGUGAUAUUCCACACGAAGCCUUUCUAUGGAGGGAAAGUCCACAGGGUUACCGCAGAAGUGAAGCACAACCCAACCAACACCAUUGUUUGUAAAGCCCAUGGGGAAUGGAAUGGUACUUUAGAGUUCACCUACAACAAUGGAGAAACCAAAGUCAUCGACACAACCACACUGCCAGUGUAUCCCAAGAAGAUCAGACCUCUUGAGAAGCAGGGACCCAUGGAGUCCAGGAACCUCUGGCGGGAGGUGACCCGAUACCUGCGGCUGGGGGACAUUGACGCAGCCACCGAGCAGAAGCGGCACCUGGAGGAGAAGCAACGGGUGGAGGAACGGAAGCGCGAGAACCUCCGCACACCAUGGAAGCCCAAAUAUUUUAUCCAGGAGGUAACUCUGCCGCCUGUCAUUGGUCCCUUGCCCAGGAGAGAACUUGUCCUGAGAGGGUAGAUGGGUUUUUCUUGCUGAGCCCCCAAGACUGGAUAAAUACCAGGCAGGGGAAGGGAUGGACUAGGGCAGCUCGGUUCUGACUCCAGCUUUGGACAAGGCUUCAGGACAGGUUUUCUGCCACAAUAUUCAUGAAACCUUCUGGAGGGCAGAACUGAGCAACUGACACUUCCCCUCCAGUAUCCCUAUGUCAGAAAAGCAUGUCAGCCUGCCUGUGAGGGAUCGCGAUGGGACUGCAGACUGGAUACUGUUCUAUUUUUAAAAAGAAAAUCAUCAUGGCACCUGUUAGAUCAUCUUUAGUAACAAAUUAGUUGAGGAGUGCCUCACAGGCCAUCUCAACACCUGGGUGGGCUGGAGCCCUCACUGAUGAAGAAUUGCCUUUCAGAGCUUUGCCUCCUGUGGGCCACAAGGGCUAGUCAUGCAGGGGAAGGCCAGCCUGAGUCCUGUGCCUAAAAUGCUGUUGCUGUCACCUGCAAAUGUGACACUAGAAGCUAGAAAUAAUAUCUGGGCAAGUGGGCAGGGCACUGUGUGCCCAGCUGAAGCCCUUAUGCUCUUGAAGUUGUGGAGGGAUUGGGAAGCACUCUGAGAACAGAAUUGGAAAUUAUGAAAAUGUAGGAGCCACACGUCUUAAAGCAGGCCCACAGGAACCCAGCAACAUCAAUGAAGAGCAGGCCGGUGAGGGCUGGGGCAGAUGCCACUCAUCUUCCAGUGAUAAAACAGAUUGUCUAGUUGUUCAUGAGGAGCCAGAAAUCUAAAUUUUUAUGAGAAAUCUCAUAUUUGCAUGGUCAAAGAUUUAAAAAAAUUUAAAUACCAGUAGGCAAUCAAAAUGUAUCUGUGGGCUUUCCUUAGCCCAGGUGCUGGUAACCCCUGACUUCUGCUACAAAGAGGGAUUAUUCUGUCUAUAUACGAGGCUGAGAAGUGAGUUAGGGCAACAUAGUAGGUAACUGGGGUGGAUUCAUGGUUAAGAGCAGGAAGAGCAGGAAGCCACCACUGUUCUCCCCAGAGUCAGGCUGUGGACUGAAGGAGAUUUCAAGGUUGGAUUCUGGUUCAGACAGGAAAGCUGCCUGGAGAAGACUUUGCCUUUAUGGGUCACUGAGUGGGGACCCUGUGUGGGAGCCCUGCCCAGGUGAGGUAAAACCUUGAAAGAUCCUUCUGUGAGGUUAGCUCCCUUUUCUCUUGAGGGAGCUAGUAGCUUGAGAGAGCUAGUUUGUCUGGCUUCUGUGGAAGGCUGUGCAUUAAACAGCAACAACAACAAGAAAAAACAUUUACAGUUCUUCCUGAGUUUAAGAAAAGCCAGUAUGCCCAUAACAGAAGGGCUGGGAACAUGUAAGGAAUAAGAGUCAUCUGAACACCAGCACAGUUAUUCAGUAUAGUGCCUUCUAGUCAUAACUAGAUGGUAUUAAUACCAUUUUAAUUCUUGCCUUUUUCUCACUUGAUAUUUGAUUGAUGGUGUUUCUUGUGUGUGCUGAUUUGUUUGUGACUACUGCCUGCUGGAGAGAGCCUUUGUUGGGUGUUCCCCUGUGGGCUGGAAGUCACUGGUAUGCACACCCUUGCCUUUUCUUUCCCCUGGCCAUUCAUCUAGCUACUCUCCUUUUCUCUUGUCCCACUGUCAAAGUGCUUCUUUUUUUUGGCCAAGUAAUCAGUCUCGAUGGAAGCCAACCAAGCUCCCCUUUUAUUUUGCUCAUUUCUUGGGGUUUCCUCCUGCCAUGCCAGGGUAGGAAGGUCAAGGUCAUCUAGAUCUCCAAAGAGCAGCUGGGCUGAGGAGGGGUACUGAGGCCAGCAGCCUGGCCUGCGUGUGAGGUAUUAAGACACGGCAGACACACAGAGUGGCUGCGGUUAUCCUUGCUUCCCCUUUUCCCUGUUGAGAGGUCUCCAUGUAAUAAUGCCUCCUUUCUUCUC